CACGCGGCACGGAGAGUGGGCCGGUGAUAGGCGACAGUGUGGGAGCUGGGGUCAGAGUUCAUAGGGUCGCAGAGGCCGCGUGCCGCGUCUCCCUCCAGUCCCCGGGGGACUGACCCCCACAACAACCCCGUGCCGCCGUUCCGGGCCCCUCCUUCCAACGGCCACGUGCGGCCUGCGCGUGCGCACUCGCCCAGUUUGGCGCCCACCAGGCAGUGGGGAAGGGGAAGGGGAAGGGGAAGAGGGUGAGGGUGGCAGGGUGGGGACAGGGAAUGGGAAGCAGUGGUGGGGAUGUGGGUGGUGGACCAGGGGCGAGGGCAGGGGACAAUGUCUGUGGAGAAGGGGGGUCUGUUUAGGUUUCCGCUCUUGGACGGGAGGGAGCGGCGGGGUAAGCAGCCUAGGAGGACUAGGGAGCUCCACAAGUCCCGCGGCCAGGGCGCCCCAAGCGAGGCCGGGGUCCGCGAACGGUCGCCACUGGAGCGGGGCUGCAAGGGGGUGCCGAUGCUGCGAGAGAAAACCUGGGGACCUUGGAACGGGCUCAUGGUAAUUGGGAAGAGAGUGGAGCUCCUGACUAGAAACACUCGAAAGCCGAAGCUGGAGUCUGAGUACUGGAGACUGGAAGAUGUGGAAAAGACGGUCUUGAAAGGGAAGUCAGGCCCGAGUCAGGAAAGGAUGGAUGUGAAGCUGCUAUACCGUGGAGCAAGUGCAUCACAAGCUUCAGCAGAUUUGGGGAAAGACAGCCCAAGGGGUAUUUGGGGAAAGCAAGAGGUCAAACACGAAAUAAAGGCUAAAUCUAAGAGUGCAGGGAUGACAGCAGGGCCUAUGAAGGGGUCUGGGUUUGAAGAGAGGUUGAGGUCUGCUGGGGAGAAGGUAGGGACCAGUGGAGAGGACUUGAGAUCCAAUGGAUAUAAACUGGGACAGGAUGAGAAGGGGUUGAGGUCUAGUGUAGACAAGAUGAGAUCAAGUGUAGAGAAGCUGAGGUCUACUAGUGAGAAGCUGGUGUGCAGGGGAGAGAAGCAGGGGUCCAGUGGAGUGAAGCUGAGGUCCAGUGGCAGAAAGCUGAGAUCAAGUGGAGAGAAUUUGAGAUCAAGUAGAGAGAAGCUGAGAUGGAGUGGAGAGAAGCUGGGAACUAGUGGAGAGAAGCUGGGAACCAGUGAUGAGAAGCUGAGGUUGAGUGGAGAGAUGCUGAGAUCAAUCAGAGAGAAGCUGAGGUUGAGUGGAGAGAAGCUGGGAACCAGUGAUGAGAAGCUGAGGUUGAGUGGAGAGAAGCUGAGGUUGAGUGGAGAGAAGCUGAGAUCAAGCAGAGAGAAGCUGAGGUUGAGUGGAGAGAAGCUGGGAACCAGUGAUGAGAAGCUGAGGUUGAGUGGAGAGAAGCUAAGAUCAAGCAGAGAGAAGCUGAGGUUGAGUGGAGAGAAGCUAAGAUCAAGCAGAGAGAAGCUGAGAUUGAGUGGAGAGAAGCUGGGAACAAGUGAUGAGAAGCUGAGGUUGAGUGGAGAGAAGCUGAGAUCAAGCAGAGAGAAGCUGGGAACCAGUGGAGAGAAGCUGAGAUCAAGCAGAGAGAAGCUGAGGUUGAGUGGAGAGAAGCUGGGGUCAAGUGCGGAGAAGCUGAGAUCUAGUGAGGAGAAGUUAGGGACCAGCGGGGAGAAAUUGGAGGGUUCAAGAAUGGGGAGCAUAAAUGAGAAGAACAUUGAAAAAGUGGUAGAAGUUACUGGCGAUGAAAGAGUGAUGGCAUUUACUCAUGAUGAGAUGGAAAUUCCUUUUGAAAGUGUCAAAGGGAGUGAGGAACUACAAGGGACUGAGAAAGGAGUGGGAGUUGAGGGGGGCAUCUUGAGUGAAGUGAAAGAUAUCACUGAUGAAUCUGUUUCUAUGGAAAAAAAAGAUAUUAUAGGUGAAGGUACCAGUGAAUGAGGCAGAUGAAGGAUUGACACCAAAGAAGGAAAGAGGCAGACAGGAGAAGUACUGAAAGUCAGAGGAGAAAUUAGAGCCAGACAGAACAUUAUUGACACUGAAGGGGUAAAGUUGAGAAAGGAAAGGAGAGAGUCUGAGCCUAAAAUAAAAGAGAGUGGAAGUGAGGAAAAGAGCUUCUGGGGCUGAAGGCGGAGGCCAGGAUCAAAGGAAGCAAAGAGGAGUCUCUGGUUCAGAGGGAAGUGGGAACAUAUGGAGGAGAAAGAGAAGACUUGGUAAUGUGUUGACAGAGGACACUUGGAUAUUGGGAGAAAAGGUGUGACUGGGAGCUCAUAGGGAAAUGUUUGAGAAAAGGAUGGAGGAUGGGCUAGAAGGAUUUAGUCUGACACUAAAUGGGGUCUAUGAGAUGGAGAAUUGCAGCAGGAUAAAGGGUAGAUUUUGAGAGUUGUGGAAGAAGGUGCAGACUGAAGUGGGCAAAAUUUCUGAAAGAGGAGCCUGAAGAAUGAAGGGCUCCCAAGUGACAAAAGCAAGAGAGGAGAUAAGAAAGAAGUGAGAAAAAACAUAAGAAGCCACGUGCCAUAAUGGUGAUUGUGUUUGUUGAUCUCUGCCAUCCCGAGAUCAUCACUCCUAGCCUCCUCUGGAAACUCUCUGAGAGUUGGGGAAUUGUCUCUUUUAUAAGAGGCCUACACAGGCACGAGGUCAUACUUGGGCAGUUUUCGGCUUUGUGAAAAUCUCUCAGAUUGCACCGCACAGUAUACAACUGAUGAACCAGACAACCACAAUCGUUCUUUGGAUUGCAUUUUCUCCUGAGAUAUCAGACGCAUUUCACCAGGGCCACAGAAAGAAAAAUGAAGACCAAGAUACCGUGACAAAUGCCAACUACCUCAUAAGUGCAGAUAUUUUCAGUUAUCUAGGUAGCUAGAGCUUUGCAUAGGUGACAGGGAAGAUGAUGCCAUCAGAUCUGUGCUUCACAUAGAGAAGUCCGGCUUCGAGAUGGAGUCACCGGAGCAUGGUGUGCGGGCACUCAGUAAAGUGGAGAUGUGAUUACUAGAUCAUUAUGGUAAGUAGUUCAGGCCUGGCAAGGUGGCUCAAGCCUGAAAUGCCAACACUUUGAGAGGCCGAGGCAGGAGGAUUGCUUGAGUCCAAGAGUUCCAGACUGGCCUGAGCAACAGAGUGAGACCCCAUCUCUACAAAAACAAACAAAAUUAGCUGGGCAUGGUGGCAUAUGCCAAUAGUUGAAGCUACUCAGGAGGCUGAGGUGGGAGGAUCACUUGAGCCUGGGAGAUUGAGGCUGUAGUGAGCCUUGAUCGCACACCACUGCACUCCAGCCUGGGUGACAGAGCAAGACCCUAUCUCAAACACACACACACACACACACACACACACACUCUUACACACACACACACAAAAUAAAUAAAUAGUUCAGGGUAGAGAGGAUGAGGUUAUGAAUUACAGCGGAGAGAGGAGGAAUAAAAACAAGACUUGAGAGAGUAUUAAAAGUCCCAUUUAACAGAAUUGGCUGAUUAAUGUGAAUGGAUGGUGAGGAAUGAGGCGCCAGGCGCAUGGAUAGCAGUAGCUGACGUGAAAUGCUUACUCUGCAUUAGGCGUGUUACACACAUUAUCUCACUUAAUCCCACAACCGCAAUUGUAUUACUAUCCACAUUUUAUAGGUGGCAUUGAAGCCCGUCAGAGUGGUCAAUCGAAACGACAUAGCUAGUAUGUGUUGGUAGUAAGUGGUGGUGUGAGGAGGUUUUGGACCUAUGUGGUAGCUCUACCAGCUGGCUGGGUCUUCAGUGCCAUGUGAUUGGGAGGUGAAGCGACCACCCUAGUCAGCAGUGAAUGAAUGGCGGAUUCGGGCCAGAAGCCUGCUGGAACCAUCUUCUGCUCCGGAGAGCUCACAGUUAGGUGGCUCUGAUGCCACAUCGGCCAUAGAUGUGUUAUGUUUGCCCCAAAGAAUAUUUUAAGACCAUGUUUAGAAUUAAUUGGUACCUUUUUAAAAUGCAGAGAUUCACAUUAAAGAGUGAGUUUCUGGCUUUUCUUGGAAAAUGAGAAGAUCUGGCCACACUGGGCCCAUAUAGGAACUGGAGUUGCCUCUCUCUGUUUCCUUCAGCUGGGGCCUGUGCCCCCCUGUUGGCCAGGCCCCACUGGCCUGCCUGGGGUCCCUGCCACCUCCGCAGGCACCUGGGUCUGCCUUUCUGCUGUUCUGUCACGAGGUGUGCCACUCAGCUUGGCUUUGAAGCCAGGCUGUGUUUGUGCAUUGAAUGCACGCCAAGCCCAGGCCUCCACUGAUGGCUAAAUACCUUUUCUGAAUUGUAGGCAAUAUAAGAUAAAAACGUGCUGCGGGAAGUGAGAAAAACUACAUGCCCCCCCAUGCUGAGUGCCCACAGGAGGCGCACGGGUAGUGCAGGAAAAAGGCAAAUGGCCAUAGUUCCUGAAACCAGCAUAAAUUAAAACAAAAUACAAAUCAUACCCUGGCAAAUGGCAAGUAACAGCCUAUUGCCAGUAUGCGAAUCACGUUGUGAUUUUUUAAAAUUUGUUUUGUAAUAAAUAAUUUGUUUGAA